ACCGACGCGGAAGACUAUAAGCCCCAGCGGGCGACGACCGAACGCCCCCGGGAACACCGGGCCCCGAGCUCGGUCCCGCGCCCGAGGAUCCUCCACGGGGCUAGAUGGCUGCGUCGGGGGCGGGAGCGGAGGUGAGCGGGCGCUAGGGCCGCGAGCCCCCGCCGGCCCUUCCUCCAGCGCCCUGCGGACCCCGCAGAAGGCGCUCGCCUCCCUAGCCCGCAAAAACAUAUCGAUUUUUCUCGCUGUGGCAACGGGGACGUCCUGAUAGAUCCUCUGCUCCAAUAGGCAACUCCGGCCUUCCCUGCCCUGACCUGGAACCUCUGGGAGGGCUGCAGAGUAAGUGCCGCCUCUGCGCUCCGACGGAGGCACGAGGCCUGUGGAGUAGGUCCCUCUGUUCCGACAGGUGCGACACUUGGCGCUCCAUGCUUGCGGGUGCCGGGAGGCCUGGCCUCCCCCAGGGCCGCCACCUCUGCUGGUUGCUCUGUGCUUUCACCUUAAAGCUCUGCCAAGCAGAGGCUCCCGUGCAGGAAGAGAAGCUGUCAGCAAGCACCUCAAAUUUGCCAUGCUGGCUGGUGGAAGAGUUUGUGGUAGCAGAAGAGUGCUCUCCAUGCUCUAAUUUCCGGGCUAAAACUACCCCUGAGUGUGGUCCCACAGGAUAUGUAGAGAAAAUCACAUGCAGCUCAUCUAAGAGAAAUGAGUUCAAAAGCUGCCGCUCAGCUUUGAUGGAACAACGCUUAUUUUGGAAGUUCGAAGGGGCUGUCGUGUGUGUGGCCCUGAUCUUCGCUUGUCUUGUCAUCAUUCGUCAGCGACAAUUGGACAGAAAGGCUCUGGAAAAGGUCCGGAAGCAAAUCGAGUCCAUAUAGCUACAUUCCACCCUUGUAUCCUGGGUCUUAGAGACCCUAUCUCAGACAGUGAAAGUGAAAUGGACUGAUUUGCACUCUUGGUUCUUUGGAGCCUUGUGGUGGAAUCCCCUUUUCCCCAUCUUCUUCUUUCAGAUCAUUAAUGAGCAGAAUAAAAAGAGUAAAAUGGUUUCCUUCCCUUCUGUAACUUGGAGCAGGAAGUCAUGGGGGCAGAGAGGGAAAGGAGGUGGUUACUUAAGGCCCCAAUCUACCAAGUCUUCCCCACCACUUCUCCCUUGUUUUCCCCCUCUUCUACUACUUAUUUCAAACUUCUGGGAUACAAUUUCAGCUAAAACGUUUAUUUCUCACUCAAAACUUAUUUCCCCUCAACCCUAUACCCAAAGAAGAAAUAAAAUCACAGAUACAUAACAGAA